GAUUUAGGGGCAAGAGCAGGGAGCCCAUGCUCCCCUGGGGCCAUCAGAAGAGGGGGCUCUGAGUGUGGAUGGGAGGGGGCCUAUACUAGGGAAAUGGGCAGUUAUGUUCCGUAUGGACUAGUAAUCACAUUAGCUAACAGUUAUGCCAUAUGCACCUACAGUACAGCCUUCACUGCUCCAAGCACUUUACACAUAUGAAUGCCAAUCUUUAUAACCCUGUGGAGUUAGCACUAUUAUCCUCAUUUUACAGAUAAGUAAGCUGAGGCUCAGAGAGGUUAAAAUACUUGCCCAAGGUCACAAAGGUCAGGUAUACACUGGGGCUUCUGGGAUUUGAGCCAGCAGUCUGGCUCCAGAGCCUGUACCCUUGACCUGACCAUGGCUGCCCCUUGAGAAACUUCCCUGCCACUGGGGGAGUGCUGAGUGCAGAGAAGACAUUUCAUACAGGAAGUGACAUUUCAGUUACAUCUUCUGGCAAUGAAGCUCCCCCUAAAAUAAGGGGUCCUCAUGGGGGAGGAUCACCCAACCACAGCCCUUUCCAGUGCCCACUGUCAGCACAGCAGCUGUGUCCUUGCUGGUAGAACACCCCAUCUCUCACCACCUGCUUCCCAUGCUGGGCCUGGGCUUGUCCCUCCUGGGAUACCUCCAGCUACAUUUGCCUCCACCUCUCAUUAGGAACCUGGGGUGACUCCCAAGAGAAGGCCCUGGUCUCCUUAAAUAUCCCAAUUCUAACCUGCAGACACCAUGGACAUACUUAUUACUCAAAGGAUGGUUGAAUAAAGUCUUGAUCUGCAAGAAGGACAUAGACCACUGAGCCCCAAGCUGACAUUCCCCCAGUGUUCCCUACUUACAGCCCCAGGAAAUGGGUCUGGGCAAGGAAGGAGAGGCUGGGGACUCUUGUGUGUAGAGGGGCUUCAUAUGCGCUGACAUGCCCCCUCCACCUCUUUGUGCAGUCAAAGCCUGCCUCCCACUCCAUUCCCGACCCCCAGCUCUCCCUGCUCUGUUCCUAGUGUCUGCCUGGCUGGCCCAUUCUGCCUUCCCUGGUCAGCCCAUUCUGCCUUUCCUGGUCUUGCCCGCUGAGUCUCCUUCCUUUGACCCCAGGCUCCUGCAGUGGGCAUCAGAACAGCCUCCUUUGAAGGGGCAGUUCCUCAGUGGCCUCACUGUUUCCUUCUGAGUGUUCUCAGACCCACUGCUGUGUCACUAUAGGGCACCAGGGCCCAGUGAGGACUGAGAUGGGGACAUAUCCUUUUUCCUAUCAGCUCCUGGGAAACAGAACAGUCAGAGGCUUCUAAGGGGCUGGACAGAGGGGCCACUCAGCACACAGCUGAGGAUAUCUUCUGUUCAUAGAGAGAAGUGGGUGGUGCAGGAUACAUUUCAUGACAUACACUCCUCAAAAAUAUUGAGCCCAGAACAAAUGGCUCAGGCCGACCUCAGCGAUUCUAGCAAUUGCCAUUCAUGCAACCUGCAUGGGAAAUUUUCUGUGCUGAUUCAAGACCAAGAGACACAUAUACUUCUCCCCUAAAACUCAGGAUCCAUGACUACCCAUUUCAAAACAAAGAAAUCCAAGAAGAUCUACCUGGUAUACAUUACAGUGCAUUUUUUUAAGACAUAUAUUAUAAAAGCAGACAGAGCUCCAUUCCGCCAACAAAACACAAUACAACUAGUGCAACAUACCCUCAUUAUGUUAGGGCAGGACAUGAGGGGGCAGCAAGAACUACCAGGAAUCCAUUUGUACCACAGGGAAGUGGCUAUCAGAACAUUAAAGGAAGUGAUGUUGGCACAUUUUAUUGGCAAGAGGAUUCACCACGAGGAAGAAAAGGCCAGAAGGCGACUCCCGGUAAGGAGCAAGGCCCACAAAUCCUCGGGUGAGUCUGAGGGAGGAGGUGGUGGCUGUGGGGUCAGCAGGUGGACACCUCCAUCACGUGGCUCCCUCUGCUGGGCUUGUGGCCCCAUGUGCAAUAGAGAAACUAAUGGAAGGUUGAGUCACCCAAUCAGAAACAAGCUGGCCAGACGUAAUGGCUCACACCUGUAAUCCCAGCACUUUGGGAGGCCGAGGCAGGUGGAUCACCUGAGGUUAGGAGUUCGAGACCAGCCUGGCCAACAUGGCAAAACCCCAUCUUUACUAAAAAUACAAAAUUAGCUGGGCUUGGUGGUGCAUGCCUGUAAUCCCAGCUACUCUGGAGGCUGACGCAGGAGAAUGGCUUAGAACCCGGGAGGCGGAGUUUGCAGUGAGCCGAGAUCGUGCCACUGCACUCCAGCCUGGGCAACAGAGGGAGACUCUGUCUCAAAAAAAAAAAGAAAGAAAGAAAAGGAAAAAAAAGAAACAUGAAGCUGAAGCUGAGAUGCGCUUGCCACUCCAGGGGCAUCCUGAGCCUUUGGAAAGAACCCAUCGACAGGGUUCUCAGAAACAUCAGAGCCACAUUUUCUCAGGGGGGCCUCCCUGUCUCUCCAGAACCCAGCUCCCAGCACCCCUAAGGACAGAGCCUGCCCAGCUCUGCCCGUGUCACUUCACUGACCCCCACCCCUGCCAGGCUUCGCCCACACCUGCAGGGCCAGCACCCAACAUGCUGAGAGAAUGGGGACCCAGAACCAGAUGAAUACAUCAGGGGAAACCGAAUCCAUUCUCUCUUGGGGUCCUGAGCCUCCCAGUGACAGAAGAUCCAGGAGAUGCGAGUGGGAGGUCGCCCUAACAGGAUCUAACAUCAUGCUCCAGAUUGCUGAAGGAACACAGAUCGGUGCCUCCUCUCCUUGACUCUACCCUCCUCACUCCUUAGCACCAGGCCUGGCUGUACAUCCCUGCCAAGGUGCAACUAAGACCUUCACCUGCAGCUCAGGGGUGCCCCAGACAGGAGCACAAGAGGAGGCUCAUCCCCACCCACAACCCAGGCCGGAGCGAAUCUGGCUGCCCAGGCUCUGUGUCUGGCUUCUGCCCCAGGACCUGAGCCCGUGUAAACUCAGGCUUCCUUGGCCUGCCCUCCCCAGGCCCAGGUUCUAAAGGUGUGCUCCCCACCACUUCCUUGUUGCUCCUCCACUUUGUCCCUAGAAUUACAGCCCAGCUCUAGGUGGGACUGUGAAGCUCUGCCCAAUGCUUUCCACAAGAAGUCAGAUUCAGGCCCUUGUGCCUGAAGACUCCUUGUGAAGACUAGAUGACACCUUCUCCAAGAGCAGCUAAGGAAUCACCUUGGUUCCUCAGGCUGAGUAUACAUUUUCUGUACGGAACUUCAGAAAGAAAUGGUCAACAUUCAUUCCUCACUUCACCAGAGAAAGAAGAAAAUGUCACGUGCCUUUGAUUCCCUCUUUUUACCAAGACUCCACUGAGAUAAAACUCCUAACACAGAAACCAACACAUAUUCUCAACACUGGGUACCUGCUGGAGGUCCUGCCUUAGCCCCGAAGCCUCAGGUUCCCAUGGGGACAGGUUGGUUGAGAACUGGUGGCCUAGCUCUCAGCCUGACACCCAACAGUAUCCCCACCCAGGAGGCAGAUGGUAGUGCAGGCACAGGUUCUGCAGGCUUUCAUCUCGUGGAACGUAUGUUAGAGGGUGUCCUCGUCACUCGCCAUGCCCCAGAGGAAUCAGCAGGGACAUCAGGACUGAGAGAAGACAUGGCACAUGUGACCUCCUGUCCUGGAAACCCCACAUCUUUCUGACUGUGCUGAUCACACGGACAAUAUCUAGAAAAGUUCUGCUCUGCACAGUGUUCUGUCUACCAGGCCCACCCAUCUGAGGACCCAGAUGCUAGGAACACACAGAUACUGAAGGAGCAACCACCUGCCUAAGGUGCAGGUACCCCUGCAUCCAUCUGUAGGAGGAAAAGCAAGAAACUACCAUUUAUAUGGAUUCUUUGGCCCUAAGAAUGAACCACCUAUUUAGGAGUAACACAGUGAUGCAGAAUGACCAGGGAGGGUCUUUCUCAACCAUGCUCCCUGGUCAUUCUGCAUCACUACAAUACACAUAGAAUCCCCAGAAUACACACCUAUUAAAGCCUCAAUAUUCUUGCUUCAUACAAACAUUUGCUUACAGAUCCUGAACACACACACCGCCCCCCACCCCAGUGGUGUGUUGCUAACUGCUUAAUAAAAUGCUCUCCAGGGGGAAAUAGGAAAGCCUAGAAUUGUGAUGCUUAAGUGGUGUAAGUAUCUCAGCAUGACUAAUUUUAAACUACCAACCUAACGCCACUGAACACAGAGAUGAGAAGAGAUGUGCUGUGCCCAAUGGCUACCCCAAGCCAGUACAAGCCAGCUCCAGCACAGCCACAUCCUUUCAUAGGAAUAUGUGUACACAAUCUACCUGCACCCUGAGUAGGACCCACAACUCUCACCCCAAAUAUAAAAACAAAACCAAACGAUGUACCUCCAGAACACAACCUCCUCAUAUAUCCUGAACAGACACACACAACUGAGAUAGGAUAGGGUGGCCAUAGCCUCCAUUAAAGGAGAACAACCUUGCUAAACAGAUGAAGAGAACAAACCAUCCGACAGUGCACAAGGAGGUCCUGCAGUAAGGAGGUGGAAAAGAAGAAGGGGAAAUCCCCAAAUUCGCACAAGUGCGAAAACCCAUGAUUAGUGUCCCUGGGUUGACCAGUGCUCACUAUAACAGUGAAAAACACACCCUUGGGUAGAGAUUUAAGAUGUUAAUGAUUCACCUGAUAUAGGCACUAGCAUGUGCAGCAAUAGCGCAUGCACGUCCAGAGAACAGUCCAGAGAGUGCUUAACAGUGACACCCCUUCCCACCCCUUCAUGAAUAGUCAUGUAAGGCUCCCAUAAAGGAGGUUUCCCCAGUGUCAGUCAAUGCUGUCUCACCUUUGAGCAGCCCACUCUGAUCGGCUGUCAGAGUGUACAUUCACUUUGCAGUAACCUCUCUUGCUUACUUUUACGUUGGACUCACUCUCAAAGUAAGACUUCUUUUGUGCAGCAAAGUCAAGAACCUGAACCAGCCCACCAGCAACACAACUGCUACCUGUACCCUAAAUACACAGAUGGCCUGCACCAAUUAUUACUUAAAUUUGCAGACAAAACUCUACCUGCCCCAAAUGCUCACCUCACUGCUAAAACCAUAUAUGUACAUAUAUACGUGCCCAAAUACAAACACGUACAAUGAACACAGUACCCAUAUAUACCCAUAUAUAGUGUGAACCCUGAAAGGGCUGAUCAUGAGUGGCUAACUGGGCCUAAACUCAAAAUGGAGCCAAGCAGCCAUUUGCUGACUGCAAGUCUCACACAUUUACCCUGUUUCCUGCAAAAACCACGUACUUGUGUUACUUUGGGACUUUCACAGCUGUCUGUUCCUGUUUAUGUCACCUGAAUCAAGGGUUACCAUUUCAUCAUAUGGACUUAAGAAAUAGACUGUGACUUGCAUCAGCCAAUCAGAAAUAAACAAGCUUGUAUCCCUCAUUUGCAGAGUGAACCAGAUCGGGAAUCUGAGAACGAAUUUCUCUGUAAAAGAUAAUACCUCUCUUUGUUCUUUCAGAGUGUAUCUUUGUUUUGCACUGAAGGCUGGGACUCCUUGAUUUGCAAACAGCUCAGUGGAAUCAAAUUUCUAUUUUUUUCUUUUGUUAUUUUUUUAAGAAAAUCCUUUUCAGUAGAUUUGUUAACAGUACAUAAUGAAAAUCCUAUAGGCAUAGGCUCAAAAAAAAAAAAAUCACAAGGUAUACAACACUUGUGUCAUGCAUCACCCAGAAAAAGAAUCACAUACAAUCCCACAGCUCUAAAAUACAGGAAUCCAUGAUUCUUGAAUCCAAACACAACCUACACAGCCUCUCUGUUUCCAAAUACAUGCACUGAACCUCCCACAUCUCCCAGAAUACAAAACACAGAAGCCACAUAAACUCAAAUACACACAGAACCACAAACUAUUUUUAUCAAAUACAUAUAAGUCCACCUCACGAACUCUGAGAACACACAUACAAGUGGCAACACCAAAUUCUGCGAGUAUUACAUUUCACAACAGACACAGAGGACCACUAAGUCUUAAUAUACCCCAAACCCCUCAUAUACACACUCACAAACUACCCAUGAAUACACACCUCACCCUCCCAGAUAAAACCCAUACAAUACAAAAAAAAAAAAACCACAAAAACACCAAUAAUACUCUAAUAUACGCACACAACUUUCAUAUACCCAUGGGCACAUACAAACUCACACAAAUAUCCCCAAUCCCUGAGUGUAUAAAUCCCCCGAAACACUAUCCAAUCAAUAUGCUACAUCUCCGGAAUACAACCUCCUCACCUCAUCCCCUAAACAUGCCCAAACACAUGUACGAACAUCCUAGCAUUCUCCAAAGAAAUACACUUUAAAUACUAACAAUCCCGUAUUCUAUAAACAGACUUAGAUAAUUCAUCUAUCUGCUGAUAAAUAUACACACAAACCAGUAUACACACCCAAGAUGCACAGAAAUAUCUCCAGCAUAUCAUUUAUAAAUACCCAUAAAAACAGUUCCCAAUCCCAAAUUAUCCCAAUCUAGUAUGAACCAGCUCCCACAUUGCCAAGUACUAACCAAUAACCAUAUCACAUACCUCUAAUACAUAUAAAUUCAACUCUCCCACUCUCCUGUAUAAAAAGAGAACCUCAUCUCUCUAUCAGACACACACAUACUAAAUUCCCAGAAUAUAUAACCCUAAUAACCACUUACUGAAAAACACAAGCACAUAGCUCCACAAAACCUUCAUCUAAACUGCCACGCCCUUGAACACACCCACAGACUCAAUACUCAUGUAUUUGUCUACAUGCCCUAAAUAUACCCGCGAUUAACUAACACGCCACAAAUAUGCAAACAUGCCACCUUAUAUCCCCAAAUACACAUACAGUUCCACAAUACCUGCACAUAUGUAAUCACACUUCCAAAUGCUCACACAGAAAUAACUCCUCCAUCUUCCAAGACACAGAAUCAUAUAAACUCCACCUCAUAACUGCACACGUUCAUCCUACCAGUCCCCCAGUAGACAUGGAUCUGCCCUCACACAUUGAAAUAGCCAUACACACCCCCUGAAAAUAAUGAAAAGAAGCACGCAUCACCAUGCAACAUGCCCUGAGUAUACAAAUGGUCUUCCUACAUUUCCCAAAUACGUAAACCAAACAGAGCGUACAUCCACAAAAUAGACACAAGCACUUUCUCUGUUAUUGCCCAUGUGCACAAGAUAAUUCUUCCAAAUCUGCCAAACAUUAGACAAAUACAAAUCGCCAACAUUCAUCUGAGAAAACACAUGGAAAAUACAUCUUCACAACCCAAAUCACAAAUAUAUAACCCCAAUUCUUCUGGUAUACAUAUCUUACAUCUCAUAUUCUCCAAAUAUAAACUCUCACUCCUACACACUCUCACAAAAACAGUUAUGACCUUCUUUUUUAGGGGGCGGGGAAUGGAGUCUCGCUCUGUUGCCCAGGCUGGAGUGCAGUGGCACGAUCUGGGCUCAUUGCAAACUCCGCCUCUUGGGUUCAAGUGAUUCUUCUGCCUCAGCCUCCCGAGUAGCUGGGACUACAGGCAUGCACCACCACACCCAGCUAAUUUUUGUAUUUUUAGUAGAGACGGGGUUUCACCAUGUUGGUCAGGCUGGUCUCAAACUCCUGACCUCAGGUGAUCCAUCUGCCUCGGCCUCUCAAAGUGCUGGGAUUAUAGGUGUGAGCCACCGUGCCCGGCCCAGUUAUGACAUUCUUUAAUCUGCAGUCUCCACACAGACACCACCAACCCACACAUGUGAAUACAUAUUAGAUUCUCACCAAUUAAAUACAUAUCAAAUUCCAAACUAAGAAUUCAUAUAAACAUAUUUUCACAUACACAAAACCACCCGCACAAAUCUCACACCCUCCAAAAUCCAAAAUAAAUCUUCCUGACAUUCUCAAGUACACACUAACCCAACCACCCAAGAUAACACACGUGUGUGCAGUAAAUUUUAGAUACAUGUGUAGCCUACAAUUUACAAAUAAUAUACCACUACUUUUUAUAUGUAAAUCCCACAUAAGUAAGCGAUUGUCAUGGAAGCUUUUCUUGACUUUGGCCACACUCUUGCAUCCACAACCAACUUGUGCUACCAAGCGAACAAACUAUGACUAAAGGACUGUUCUUCCACUUUGCAGCUGCUCCUAUCAGUGACAAAUCAGCGUAUUAGAACAUGCAUGCUGGCUGAUCAUUCUGAUCAAGUCAACAAGCUUCACAACUUACUCAAUGAGGUCGUCCGUGAGAACUUCACUGUUUUACGGGGACAGGAGCUACUUCUUUGCUGAACUGCAUCACGGUUUCAACUGCUGAGGUUUUCUUCAAGCUUUUGCAUUGUUUGGAAUGUGAAAGGCACGGCCGAGACACACUUUGAGGUUCCCACUGCAUUGUUACACCUCCCCCCUCACUUCAGGGCCAGGUAACACCAAGAAGGACGCCAUGAGAGCGAAGGCCGGUGGGUCACCGCCCUUUGCUCUCGUGCUGCGCGUCUCCCUGCCAUCAACCGCCGCAACCGGCGCUGGGAGCGGUUGAGGGCGGCCGGCCUCGCGCUGGAACCUCGCCCGCCUCAAGGCUCCUGCGGCGGCACACGGGGCAGGCCAGGAGCCCGCCCUAGGAGGGCCCCGCUGGAGAUGUGGAAAUGGAGGGACGCGGCACCUGGGUGCUUCCUGGGGCCAGACAACGCCCCCUCAUUGGAACCUCCAUGACCGUGCCUCUGAGAAACCAGCGCGUCCGCAACGAUCACUCCUAAUUUUCGGAUUCCUAUCAUCUGUCUCCACGUGAUAACACUGAAGAGCCUUCACGUUGAUGCAGUCCCAGGGCCUCAAGUGCAGAGUCUGAGAGCUCUGCAGGACACAGCAUGGAGCCGCCAUUCCUCUACUGGGUGGAGGAGCAUGUGUCCUCUGAACAGGGGAUCCAAGCCCUGAGAUGUUCUUUCUCAGCUGUCAGUGCGGCCCAGGACUUUCUGUGGGGAUGCUCAGACAGCAGGGGCCGGAGGACUUUUAGCCACCACCUCCCAUGGCCAGUCUUCACAAAUUACCUUUGGCUAAUUUGACUGUCUCUCCUCCUGGGGUCUAGGACUUCAAACAUGUACAGAAGCGAUUGCAGAAUUAAGACAAGACACUUCCACAAUAUAUUUUUUGUAUCACUGGCUCAGAAAAAGACUCAUUCAAAUCCUGUAUCAAAGCCACGUGUGAGAAUCUUGAGAAAGCAUCAGCUGACUGACUUGACAAGGGAGGAAGCAACCAAAAAUUCUGCGCUUCUUCAGUAUCUGAGUAUGAUAUUUUGCUUCAACAUCCCUCUUAGAUGAAGUUAUUGAUUGAAAAUCAUUUAAGUUUGCCCCAUGGUAAAAGAUCAAGUCCUCAGAAAGAUCUCCAAAGUGUUUACGGUUUGUUUUGUUUUGGUAAGUUUACCAUGAUUUUGCUUGAAUUGCUCUCCGUUGAUCUUCUCAGCUAAGAUGGAGGUAGAGUUGCACAGUGGAAGAGGGCUGCAUGUAAGAAGGCAGUUCUGUCUCAGAGGACAAAAGGCCUGGGAGCACCCAGACAGUCACUGCAUGGAGGUCACUCCCCUCCCAGUGGCCACUGUGGAGACAUUUCACAGAAAUGCUUGCUGGACCAUUCAGGUUCAGAGUUGGGACAAAACCGAGAACUCAUGGGGAUAUUGGACAGGAGUUAGGAAAUGACCUUCUCACACAACUGGGGCAGUGGGGGAGAACCCUGGGCUUGAGACUUGCAAUCCACCACUUGCCCCUGCCCCUGCCCCUGCAGUGUGGCCGCUGUUACAUUUUCCUGCAACUCUGCCUUCUUGAGUCCAAAUGUCUUCAAAAGGGGCAAAUGCUUCGUAAGUGCCGACAGGGUGUGUUUCAGUGAAUGUUUGCAGUGUGCACCGGUCUGGCUGAAGGCCUCUUCCCUUCCCCAACACCCUCCCAUCGUGCAAAAUUACCCUGCCCAGCAGGGAGUGACUUGUGUGUCUCAGAAGAUUUUGUUGCUGUGCUCUGAGUUCUCACUCCUCAUCUCCUUUGACCAGUUUCUUCUAAUACUCCCCUUGUUCACAACACAGAACAUGAGUGCUCUUUCCUAUCAUUUUGACACUAAUAAACGGACAGUGAUUCUCAGUGUGGAAAUGAGAAUGAAGCUUUUUUUAAAGACAGGCUACAAUAAUUCCCAUGCAGAGAACCACAUGCGAUGACACUGGAUUCCAAACAGCAAGAACGUAUGGUGAAGAUGAGGCCAACAGUGAGCUGAGAGAGGCCAGCCAGGGUGUGUUUCAGUGAAGAUGAGAAACAAUCAGAUAACACCUGUUUCCUCCAGGAAAGAAAAUGUGGCCAGGGAAAAGAGAUGGGAGGAAGGCUGGUCAUUGCCUAUUCCACUGUGCACAGUUUGAAUUUGGAGCCAUGAAAAGUAUUGCUUGGUUAAAUUAAAAUCAUUCAAAAGAUAAAACAUAAACAUUUAACACCAGCACAAUAUGCUGGGAAACAAAAUGAAAGGAUUUCUGGUCUCGGUGCUGUAGGUCACAUAGCCACUCUUUCCUGGAUUGAGGCUUUCCAGCAAAGGGGCUGGGACGUAAGGCUGGCCUGCUGGUGUGGACAGAGAUUCCAGCAACAUGCAUGACCUGGGGGUACAAGGAUUGCUUCCUAAACAAUGAUAAGCACACAGCCACCUAAUAGUCUGGAUCGGCUGAGACCAUCCUGAUUUCAAACACCCAGUCCCCUUGCCUUCCUAAGAACCCCUGUGUUUCUCAGACUGAAAAUGUGUUUUGAACUUUGUUCACGAAGUGAGGCCGCUGUUGAAAUUCGUCAAGACUGGGAAAGAGCCAAAGUGGGAAGGAGCAUGGGUUGAUUGGCACAAAAGUAGGUCUGCUGAUAAAGAAUGGAAGUAAAGGGGCCAUCAGGUAGAAGCUUUUGCUGUGAGUCAGAAGGACAAUUUAAAAGUUGCCUAAAGAGGCACACGCCAUCUCUGCUGCUGCCUUCCAGUUGGAAGGGAAACUCAGGUUCUUGCCUAAUGGCCGAAGCCCUUCACAGAACGUCCCCCACCCCUAACAGCUGCCCACUGCCCCUCCCCCUCUGCAGAAUGUCUGGGGUCCUAUGUUCCAGGAACCUGUUUACUUUCAAAUUUUCCCUGUUUCAGUUGGACUCAGGAGCAUCUGGUGAGCCAGGUCACUCUCUGGGUCUUACCCUUGGCUUUUCUUAUUGCGGAAACUGCCAGACGGCGGUGGUCAGUGCCCAGCCUGAGGGGAUGGCUUCGAAUGGAGCAUACCCAGUGCUGGGACCGGGCGUGACCGCGAACCCUGGCACCUCCCUGUCUGUGUUCACGGCUCUGCCCUUCACCACACCCGCUCCCGGCCCAGCACACGGGCCGCUCCUUGUGACUGCAGGGGCUCCUCCAGGCGGCCCUCUGGUGCUGUCUACCUUCCCCAGCACACCUCUGGUGACAGAACAGGAUGGCUGCGGCCCGAGUGGGGCCGGGGCUUCCAACGUCUUUGUCCAGAUGAGGACAGAGGUGGGGCCUGUGAAGGCCGCUCAGGCGCAGACCUUGGUCCUAACUCAGGCCCCCCUCGUCUGGCAGGCUCCAGGCGCCCUCUGCGGAGGUGUUGUGUGUCCACCUCCCCUACUCCUGGCAGCUGCUCCUGUGGUGCCUGUUAUGGCUGCCCAGGUGGUUGGGGGCACCCAGGCCUGUGAGGGAGGCUGGUCCCAGGGCCUUCCUCUUCCACCACCACCACCACCGGCUGCCCAGCUGCCCCCCAUUGUGUCCCAAGGGAAUGCUGGGCCAUGGCCACAAGGGGCUCAUGGAGAGAGCAGCCUGGCUUCCUCCCAGGCCAAGGCCCCGCCAGAUGACUCCUGUAACCCCAGGAGUGUCUAUGAGAACUUCCGACUCUGGCAGCACUACAAGCCCCUGGCCCGGAGGCACCUUCCCCAGAGUCCUGACACCGAAGCGCUUUCGUGCUUCCUCAUCCCAGUUCUCCGAUCGCUGGCCCGGCGGAAGCCCACCAUGACCCUGGAGGAGGGACUGUGGCGGGCCAUGCGGGAAUGGCAGCACACGAGCAACUUUGACCGGAUGAUCUUCUACGAGAUGGCGGAAAAGUUCCUGGAGUUUGAGGCUGAGGAGGAGAUGCAGAUUCAGAAAUCGCAAUGGAUGAAGGGGCCCCAGUGCCUGCCUCCUCCAGCCACACCGAGGCUUGAACCUCGAGGACCCCCGGCCCCUGAGGUGGUCAAGCAGCCAGUGUACCUUCCCAGCAAGGCCGGCCCCAAGGCCCCGACUGCCUGCCUGCCACCACCCAGGCCCCAGAGGCCAGUGACCAAGGCCCGCCGGCCACCACCCCGGCCCCACCGGCGAGCAGAGACCAAGGCCCGCCUGCCACCACCCAGGCCCCAGAGACCAGCAGAGACCAAGGUCCCUGAGGAGAUCCCCCCAGAAGUGGUGCAGGAGUAUGUGGACAUCAUGGAGGAGCUGCUGGGGCCUUCCCUCGGGGCCACGGGGGAGCCCGAGAAACAACGGGAAGAGGGCAAAGUGAAGCAGCCACAGGAAGAGGACUGGACGCCCCCAGACCCGGGCCUCCUGAGCUACAUUGACAAGCUGUGUUCCCAGAAAGACUUCGUCACCAAGGUGGAGGCCGUCAUUCAUCCCCAAUUCCUGGAAGAAUUGCUUUCCCCAGAUCCACAGAUGGAUUUCUUGGCCCUAAGCCAGGACCUGGAGCAGGAGGAAGGACUCACCCUUGCCCAGCUAGUGGAGAAGCGCCUCCCACCCUUGAAGGAGAAACAGCAUGCGAGGGCAGCCCCUAGUCGUGGCACAGCCCGGUUGGACUCAAGUUCUUCUAAGUUUGCAGCUGGCCAAGGAGCAGAGAGAGACGUCCCUGACCCCCAACAAGGGGUUGGCAUGGAAACCUGCCCACCCCAGAUGACUGCCCGGGACUCUCAGGGACGAGGCAGAGCACACACUGGCAUGGCCAGGUCCGAAGACUCUGUUGUGCUUUUGGGAUGUCAGGAUUCCCCUGGGCUGAGGGCUGCCUGGCCAACCUCUCCUCCCCAGGACCACAGACCCACCUGCCCUGGCGUGGGUACCAAGGAUGCCUUGGAUCUCCCUGGAGGGUCUCCUGUCAGGGAGUCACAUGGGCUGGCUCAGGGGUCAAGUGAGGAGGAGGAACUCCCCAGCCUGGCCUUCCUCUUGGGUUCCCAGCACAAGCUUCUGCCCUGGUGGCUACCCCAGAGCCCUGUCCCUGCCUCGGGCCUUCUCAGCCCAGAAAAGUGGGGACCCCAGGGAACUCAUCAGUCCCCAUCUGCUGAGAGAAGAGGCCUCAACCUAGCACCUUCUCCUGCCAACAAGGCCAAGAAGCGACCUCUCUUUGGAAGCCUGUCCCCUGCUGAAAAGACACCCUACCCAGGGCCUGGGCUCAGGGUCUCUGGGGAGCAAUCCCUGACUUGGGGGCUGGGUGGCCCCUCACAGUCUCAAAAGAGAAAGGGUGACCCCUUGGUCUCCAGGAAGGAGAAGAAGCAGCAUUGUAGCCAGUAGGGGCUUCUGAGCAGGCUCUCUGGGGCCAAUCCCCAAGGAUGGGGCUCUGGCAUCCGAUGCCCCAAAGCGGUCAAAAGCUUCUUCUCCCCCAGUGCUGAUCUUGCUGGGCCUUAGCUUUGGAGGGUAGGGGAGGGAGGGGAGGGAGAGGGUGGCUGAAUGGGGAGGGCAGGAAGGGAGGGUCUGGGGGGAAGGGGCUGGGGAGUGGGGGUGGGAAGCAGUGCGUUGGGGGCCUCGUGUGUAAGUGUGAAUAAAUGUAGUUGUCUUGGAAAAUGC